ACAGGCGCCUGCGCCGCAGCGGGGCUGCCGCUGGUUGGUCCGCACGUGGAACCUCUCCUGGUCCUGUUGACCCGGGCCCCUCGGAACCUCCAGCUUGGUCCGGUCUGGGACUGGAAGCCUGCCAUGGCGGCUUCUGCGGCGGAGACGCGCGUGUUUCUGGAGGUGCGGGGACAGCUGCAGAGCGCGCUUCUGAUCCUGGGAGAACCGAAAGAAGGAGGUAUGCCCAUGAAUAUUUCCAUAAUGCCAUCUUCACUCCAGAUGAAAACCCCUGAAGGCUGCACAGAAAUCCAGCUUCCAGCAGAGGUCAGGCUUGUACCUUCCUCUUGCCGUGGGCUACAGUUUGUUGUUGGAGAUGGACUGCACCUGCGACUGCAGACGCAAGCAAAAUUAGGCACAAAACUGAUUUCAAUGUUUAAUCAAAGCUCGCAAACCCAAGAAUGUUGCACGUUUUAUUGCCAAUCCUGCGGUGAAGUCAUAAUAAAAGACAGGAAGCUCCUCAGGGUGCUCCCACUGCCGAGUGAGAACUGGGGAGCUCUAGUUGGAGAAUGGUGUUGUCAUCCUGACCCCUUUGCUAAUAAAUCACUUCAUCCGCAAGAGAAUGACUGUUUUAUUGGAGACUCUUUCUUCUUGGUGAAUUUAAGAACCAGUUUGUGGCAGCAAAGACCUGAACUAUCCCCAGUGGAGAUGUGCUGUGUUUCUUCUGACAACCAUUGUAAAUUGGAACCAAAGGCAAAUACCAAAGUAAUUUGUAAGCGUUGCAAGGUAAUGUUGGGAGAGACCGUGUCAUCAGAAACCACCAAGUUUUAUAUGACAGAGAUAAUUAUUCAGUCAUCUGAGAGGAGUUUUCCUAUCAUACCAAGGUCUUGGUUUGUCCAGAGCGUGAUCGCCCAGUGUCUGGUGCAGCUCUCCUCUGCUAGAAGCACUUUUAGAUUCACGAUUCAAGGUCAGGAUGACAAAGUGUAUAUCUUGCUAUGGCUUUUAAAUUCAGACAGUUUGGUGAUUGAAUCUUUGAGAAAUUCCAAAUAUAUCAAAAAAUUCCCCUUGUUGGAAAACACAUUCAAAGCCGAUUCUAGUUCUGCCUGGAGUGCUGUCAAGGUCCUCUACCAGCCAUGCAUCAAAAGCAGGAAUGAAAAACUUGUCAGCUUGUGGGAAAGUGACAUCAGCGUCCACCCGCUAACCCUGCCCUCUGCAACCUGCUUGGAGCUGCUGUUGAUAUUGUCAAAGAGUAAUGCCAAUCUGCCUUCAUCCCUUCGCCGUGUGAAUUCCUUUCAGGCAGAAGAGCUUCACUCCAUGACCACAACCACCAAAAACCCAUAGGGAGUACUGCCAAGCUACCGCUGAUGUUCACAUGAGGCCCAAGGGCACUUCAGUCAACUUGUGGUGAAUUCUGCCAGACUGGGACUCACCCUUCAGGGCAGUGGGCACCCCUUUGGCUCAGGACAGAUCGAGAAAUGCUGUCUAAAAACCAAGUCCUGGACUCAGGGACCAAAGAACCUGCUUUGUGCUCUACCCAACUGUGACCAAGCUAGUACCUAAAGUGCAAGACAAAGUCUCCUUUACUUUUCCCUUUGCUUUCCUCAAGCAAAAGGAGUUUCUCACCAUAGCCAUCACAGCUUCAAAUGUGUUGUGUCUCAGCUGAAGUCAGCAACUCUCAGAAUCUCACCCAAGGCCCACAGCUCACUACCUGGGUAUCACUACUGGUUAUUCAGGGCCCAGGGGCUCUUUAGUCAUCAGAUGAUAGGCUUUGCCUGGACUGGGUCCUUCCCUUUAUGGCAACAGAUUCCCUUCUGGUCCAGGAUAUGUCUACAAAUGUCAUCCAGGAGCUAGGGCCUGGAAUGGGGCCUCACAACCCUGAUCAGUUCUCUGUCAUACUGUGGCCGAGCUAGUAUUCAAGAUUCAAAAUAAAAAUCCUCUUUACUCUUCCCUCUCCUCUCUUCAAGUGAAAGGAAGGGGUCUCUUUUGGAGUUGUGUUGCCUAGAGUUGGGGGAGGGGUGGCACAAGCACUCCCUUAGCUGCCCCAGCUAGUGUCUCAGUAGGUUGCAUCACCCCCAAGUCCACUUGCUCCAAGCCCAGCUCAGCAUUAAGACUUGCAGUCUCUGUGGUCUAGGUUGUUUCAAGUUUUUUUAUGGCCCCAGAGCACUUCAGCCCACAGUAACAAAGCUUGACUGAACUCAAGUUCCCACCACUGGGAUGGGCGAUUCCCUUCUGGCUAGGGUUGAUCUGCAUGCUCCCUGCUUGUGUGGGCAUCGGCUGAGUUCCACUUGGUUUUGCUUUCCACUGUAACCAGGAAGCACUGAGUUUAAUGUGAAGUCUCAUAUUCACUGCACUCUCCCCCUUCAAGAGCACAGAUUUCUCUGAGCUGUGCAGGUGCUGUGGGGGAAUGGGAGAGGGGUGGCAUUGACAAUUCAAGACUGUUUCCUAUUCUUUUCAGUGAUAUGAAGUUAAAAUCAGAUACCAUGAGUCCUUACCUGAUUUUUAGUUCUUUUUUUGUAGUUGUUGUUUGUUUUUUGUUUUGAGACAGGGUCUCGCUCUGUCAUCCAGGUUGUAGUGUAGUGGUGUGAUCUCAGCUCACUGCAACCUCCACCUUCUGGGCCCAAGCAGUCCUCCCAACUCAGCCUCCCAAGUAGCUGGGACUACGGGUACAUGCCACCAUGCCCAGCUAAUUUUUGUACUUUUAGUGGACACGGGGUUUCACCAUGUUGCCCAGCGUGGUCUUGAAUUCCUGGGCCCAAGCAAUUCUCCCGCAUCAGCUUCAAAAGUGCUAGGAUUACGGGCAUGAGCCACCGUGCCUGGCUGAGUUUCGGUUCUUAAGAAGGUGCUUUUUUGUGUGUAGAUAGUUGUCAAAUUUGCUUUCCCUGUCAGGGGGACAGUGGAUAGGGUAUUCUAAAAAAAAGCAAGUCAGUUACUUCCUAGAUACAGUGGGGUUACAGGCAUUAGGUAAAUACACCCAUUCCACAGGGGAGAAAUUGGCCAAAACAAAGGGGCUACAGGCCCCAUGUAAGUCUGAAAUCCAAUAGGGCAGUCAUUAAAUCUUAAAGUUCAAAACUGAUCUCCUUUGACUCCAUGUUUCACAUUCAGGUCAUGCUGAGGCAAGAGGUGAGCUCCGAUGCUUUGGGCAGCUCUGCCCCUGUGGCUUUGCAGGGUACAGCCCCCCUCCUGGCUGCUUUCAUGGGCUGGUGUUGAGUGUCUGUGCAGGUGCACAGUGCAAGCUGUCGGUGGAGCUACCAUUCUGUGGUCUGGUUGAUGGUGGCCCUCUUCUCACAGCUCCACUAGGCAGUGCCCCAGUGGGUACUCUGUGUGGGGGCUCAGACCCCACAUUUCUGCUCCUCACUGCCCUAGCAGAGGUUCUCCGUAAGGGCUCUGUGCCUGCGGCAACCUCUGCCUGGACAUCCAGGCAUUUCCAUACAUCCUCUGAAAUCUAGGUGGAGCUUCCCAAACUUCAAUUCUUGACAACUGUGCACUCACAGGGCCAAUACCACAUGUAAGCCACCAGGGCUUGGGGCUUGCACCCUUUGAAACAAUGACCUGAGCUGUACGUUGGCCCCUUUUAGCCAUGGCUGGAGCUGAAUAGGCAGUGGCUGGGAUGCAGGCCUGGGCCUGGCCCACAAAACCAUUUUUUCCUCCUAGCACUCUGGGCCUGUGAUGGGAGGGGCUGCCCUGAAGGUCUCUGACAUGCCCUGGAGACAUUUUUCCCAUUGUCUUGGUGAUUAACAUUCUGCUCCUUGUAUCUUAUGCAAAUUUCUGCAGCCAGCUUGCAUUUUUUCCCAGAAUAUGGGUUUUUGUUUUCCAUCACAUUGUCAGGCUGCAAAUUUUCCAAUCUUUUAUGCUCUGCUUCCCCUUUAAAUAUAAGUUCCAAUUUCAGAACAUAUCUCUCAAAGUUCCACAGAUCUCUAGGACAGGGGCAAAAUGCCUCCAGUCUCUUUGCUAAAACAUAGCAAGAGUGACCUUUCUAUUCCAGUUCCCAACAAGUUUCUUAUCUCCAUCUGAGACCACCUCAGCCUGGACUUCAUUCUUCAUAUCACUAUCAGCAUGUUGGUCAAAACCAUUCAAUAAUCUCUAGGAAGUUCCAAACUUUCUCACAUCUUCCUGUCUUCCUCUGAGCCCUCCAAACUGUUCCAACCUCUGCCCGUUUCCCAGUUCCAAAGUCACUUCCACGUUUUGGGUAUAUUUAUAGCAGCACCCCACUCUACUGGUACCAGUUUACUAUAUUAGUCCUUUCUUGCUGCUAUAAAGAACUCCCUGAGACUGGGCAGUUUAUAAAGAGAUUUAAUUAACUCACAGUUCUGUAUGGCUUGGGAUGCCUCAGGAAACUUACAAUCAUGGCAGAAGGUACCUCUUCACAGGGCAGGAGGAGAGAGAAUGAGUGCCAACAGGGGAAAUGCCAGAUGCUUAUAAAACUAUCAGAUCUCAUGAGAACUCACUCACUAUCACGAGAGCAGCAUGAGGGAAGCUGCCCCCAUGAUCCGAUUACCUCCACCUAGUCCUGCCCCUGAUGCAUGGGGAUUCUGGGGAUUACAAUUCAAAGGGAGAUUUGGGUGGGGACACAGAGCCAAACUGUAUUACUGAAGAACUUAAAAAAUAAUAAUAUAAUAACUUAUAGGGGCUCCUAGAAAUAGAUAGACAGAGGCCUGGGAAUUUUACAGGUAAGUAGCAACAAUGGGCUAUAGACAAGAGAAAGUGAACUUUUUAUCUCUGCACUCUUUUUUUUCUAUAUACUUUCAAACAUUGUACUACAUAAAUGACCUCAUCUGUUAUAUUCCACUUUCAUCUCUGGGUGAAUUAUAGCCAUUAUUUUUUUUUAAGUCAUGUUUUCCCCUAAUUAUAUAUAUAAAAUAAAACCUUUUUUCAUAAAAAAAAUUGGAAAAUUCAUAAAAAUAUAAAGAAAAUUAAGAUCACUGGGAGUAACCAGUAUUGACAUUUUAAAGUAAUUGUUUUUUAUUUUUUUGGAGAUAGUCUUGCUCUGUCACCCAGGAUAGAGUCCAGUGGCACGAUCUCAGCUCAUUGCAACCUCCGCCUCUUGGGUUCAAGCAAUUCUCCUGCCUCAGCCUCCUAAGUAGCUGAGAUUACAGACGCCACACCCGGCUAAUUUUUGUGUUUUUAAUAGAGAUGGGGUUUCACCGUAUUGGCCAGGCUCGUCUUGAACUCCUGACCUCAAGUGAUCCACCUGCCUCGGCCUCCCAAAUUGCUGCGAUUACAGGUGUGAAGCACCGUGCACGGCCAUUUUAGAGUAAUUCUUAGUCCUAUUUUUAAUAUCUGCUUAUACACGCACACACAAAUAUAUAUAUUAAUAUAAAAUUGGGCUCAUUGAAGAUGCUGGCUGGGGCACAGUACUGACAAUACUCUGCUCUUUCCUCUGUUUCAUCUCCUGGCAUGAAGACAUAUACUUUUCCCAAGAGACUAUCAAUGGGCCUUGGGGACAUUAUAUAUGAGGGUCUCAGGGUCCUGUUAUUAACUGAGAGUGGGUAGGGAAGAAGGGUGUGAGUGAUUCCACAUGUCAAAGGGCUUCUGCAGAUGUAGUCAUGAAGCAGACAGACCUGAACCAAGAUGGGCAGGCACUCCCUAGAAUUUUCACUCAGCACUUGUGGUAAUCCACGUGUGCAUCCCAGGAAACUGAGAUGGGAGUGGUGUUGGCACCUUCGGGUCCCUGGAUGUGUCCACUAUUUUUCCUUUCCUGCUAAUGCCUUUGUCCUCAGUGUGCAAAGAUAAUCAGGACUUGAGUGCUGGUCAUUGUAUUUAGGAACUUCGUUCUCAAAGGUAGUGAUUACUGUCCUAUUUUCCAUCUCUCUCCUCAAAACAAUUUCUGAGAAUUGCCUCAGCAAUUUGGAUGUGAAAGAUGUUGUCAUCUUCAUUCCUUUUUGCCCUGCAGGGUGUUCUGUGGUCUGGGGAAAUAAGCAGGUAUUCUUAGUUGAAUACAGUUCUCUAAUCUGAAUUGUCUCAUCCUCUGCCUCCUUUCAUUUUGGACUCUCCUUUUUGCCAUACUCUAGAGAGAAUGUGGAGGAUGGGGCCAGGCAGACAGCCUGGAGGUUAACCAGAAAUUUAGUCAGAUCCACGUUGCUGCCACAUCACAUCUUUCAAAAGGCCGAUUCCCUACCCAGAUACCUGCCACGUGACCUGCCCCUCAGACAUUUCUGUCCCUACCAAGGAGUUGAGGUUGUGGGCAAAGCUGGACAGUUUCUGUGCUUUCUGUAGCACUUCGUAGGGGAGGUCUGAUGGGACUUAGGAUGCUCUGCCCUUUGCUUUAUUGAGAGAAGCAGGGAUGAUGUAUAGCUUACUAAGUCUAUAAUUAUGUUUCUUGUUUUGUUUGGUUGUGUUUAGUAAGUUAAUUUUUUCCUGAUUCUAAAGGAAAUACCGUCAUGUAUCACUUAAUGAUAGAGAUACAUUCUGAGAAACAUGUCAUGAGGCAUCACAGAGAAUGUCAUAGAGUGCACUUACACAAACCUGGAUGGGCUGGGACAGACACAAACCUAGAUGGGCUGGGACAGUCUACUACACACCUAGGCUAUGUGGUAUGGCCCAUUGCUCCUAGGCUGCAAGCCUAUAUGGCACUGUACUGAAUACUGUAGGCAAUUGUAAUACAAUGGUAAGUAUUUGUGUAUCAAAAUAUAUCUAAACAUAGAAAAGGUACAGUAAAAAUAUGGUACAAAAGAUAAAAAGUGGUGUACUCAUAUAGGGCAGCUCCAUUAUAAUCUUAUGAGACUACUGUUGUACAUGUGGUCCCUUGUUGAUCAGACAUCAUUAUGCAGCUCAUGACUGUAUGUACCCACGAUAGACGAUGUGGUAUGGGUUUUUCAUUAGCAAAACAAUACAUAUUUUUACUUUUAGCAAACUAAAAAUAUAGAAUCUUAAAAUUGAACCAAUGGCUACCUAGCCCAAUUCAGUCCAUCUGUCCUUCAUGGUGGGGAGAGAAGGCCUAGGGGCAAGGCCUGGCAGGCUCUGGGCAGCCUUUGUGAUUUGAGAGCACUCACCUUCUCUUACCUCAGUAUCUGUAACACAGAAAUGGGGAUAAGGAGAACUGGAAGACAGAUAGGGUUUGUCUAAUUCUGUGAUGACAUUAUUAUGAAUGGUACUCGUUCUUUUUUUUUUUUUUAAUAGACAGGGUGUCCAGUCUCACUCGGUCACCUUGGCUGGAGUGUGGAGUGUAGUAGCACGAUCGUAGCUCACUGCAGCCUCGAACUGCUGAGUUCAAGCAAUCCUCUUGCCUCAGCCUCCCAUGUAGCUGGGAUUAUAGGUGCAUGCCACCACACCAGACUAUGGUGCUAGUUCUUAAAUGUCAGUAUACAUGGGAAGCUUGUUUAAAAUUUAGAUUUCUUAGUGAUCUAAGAAAUCGGAGUCCUAGCCAGAGAGAUUCCGAUUCAAUAGCCCUGAAGUAGAGCCCAAAAAUCUGCAUUAACAAGCAUCCAAAAGUGUGUAUGAUAGGGAAUUUCAAGAACGAAAACUGUAAGAAACACGUGAUAAGAGAAUAUACACCAACUAAAGUGAGAAAUGAAAGAAUUUUAAUUAUAACAACAUCUAGUCACAGGUCCAAAUAGCUUAAUUAUUUUCCUCUUUUCUUCACUGCUCCUUAUUAACCUGCACUUAACACAGUCUGUAUUGCACUAAACUGAAUAGUUGUCAUCAAGUUUGUGUUUUUUUAUUUUCCUUCUCUCUUUACCCUCAGAUGUCUUGUAGAAUCCUGGUGUUACCUCUGUCACUCCUCUUUCUGCCAUUGGUGUGAACACCCGGCAUCCCCACAUCUCCUGAUAUCCGGGCUUCUUGCUUUUCUCAGGGAUGUGCAGCCUCUGUAGUCCUCUCUCUCACGGCACGUCUGAUGUGGUAGGACAGUCGCUCACGCUGAUGUCAGACACUCAAGAUCUAGUCUGGACUGCUGACCCUCUUCUAGGCAGAUAACCCUCUAUGGAUCCCAGUUUCGUUAUCUAUGGGAUGAAGGGUUGGGUUAAAUUACAUAUGUAAGUGUUUUUAAAGUUCGUUUAAAGUAGAGGCACAGAGUCAUUUUUGUCUGUUCCCAGCUGUUCCUGAUUUAUUCACCCAGUCUGCAUAAUAUAACUGUAUUCCUUAAAUGUUAUAGAACCUUAUUUCUUGUGAACAUCCUAGAAGUGUUUAACUGAGGAAAAAUAUAGAUAAAGUCAGAUUACAUAGGGUUGUUGUGUGUGUGUGUGCGCGCGCACACGCCCGUGUGCUCUCCAAGAGGAUGGAGUUGAUGCCGUAAGACCUCCCUAACAGCUGCCAGGAAGGGACAGGAAUGAUGGGGUUAGGGUGCCAUCUGGCCCUUGGCUCUUCCUGCCUCUGAGACAUAGGUAACUCUUUCAUGUGGAGGCUAGUAAAGGAAGAACCCUGUCCGAAGGGCUGUUUGUCACAGAAACUUGAAAUGUUCUCUGACAGCCCGUAAUUUCCCCCCUUUCGUCUUCCUUCUCUACCCUCCCUUAGACUUUUUGCACUUUCGGCUUCCCCUUUUAUUUUUCACUCUGGUUCUUGGUGCACAUUGAAACAUUUAUGGCUUAGGAAUUUUUCAGUGAUUUUGUCUUUGUAUUUUACUUAUAAGUAUAGUUACUCCAAGAAAGAUUUCUAAAAUGUGAGCCUCUUCUGUUGCCUGGAGCUGCUACUGAGAGGACUUCGUUCUUUCCCACACACUGAGCAUGGCUGUGUUCAGUCAAGUGGUGGGUCUUACUUCCUUGGAAAGGAGGCUAAAGAUAUGUGUCUGCUUUUAGAAACAAAGUGGGAUCAAGAUUGAAAUAACUGAGCUUGCUUCACUCAUGGAGGGAGCUGCUGUGUUGUUCUCAGGAGCUUUUUUUGUGUGUUUUUGUUUUUGUUGUUUGUUUGUUUUGUUUUGUUUUGUUAGAAGGGGGAAACAACAGCCUGGGGAGGAUGUCAGCCUUCAAGGGAAUGUAGUUUGGAAGGUGAAACUGUUCUCAAGCCUCCAUUGAGAACCUCUUGUGAGCCCUCCUGGUAGUGAGUAAUCAUUUCAGCAAAGUGAGAAUAUUUAGAAUAGAAGAGGUAUUGGGGGAUCUUUUCUAGUCUAAAUGGAAAUAAGCCAAAGGAAGCAUGGGAAACAAGAAUGAAAUUAUUUUAUUGUCCCUUUGGUCCUUGCUCUUAUAGACCUCAUCUAUGGAGCAGUAAAGAAAAGGGCCUGCAGUGGAGGUGGAAGAUAUGAUUGGGCUCCUUCAUGACUGUUAUGAAACCAGCAACCAGCGUGACUGGACCUAAGUCACUUUCCCUGUCUAUACCCUAGUGUUUUCAUUCCUCCUGCGCUAAACUGAUUCUAACUUCUAGUAGUUGAAAGUUUCACAGAAGUGUAAGAGCUUGUGGAUUAAACUAGCCUGAAAAAGAAAAAUUAUCAUCCAGUUUGCCCUUCUCUGAGAUUAGCACAUUGCUUCUUUGGGGUUUGGAGGUUGGAAGUGAUGGUCACAAACCAAGUGAUCAUGUCUGGGCAGCAGGGAAGGGGCUUCAAUUAGGGGCUUAAAGCAAUUAGCAUCAACAGUUGGCUUUCAGAAAUUUAAGACAGUGUGAUUAAUCCAUAGCAUACAAAGGUUGUCUGGUAUAUAGUCCAAAGCUGUGAUAACAGAGCACAGACUAAAUUGGCAGAAUAAUGUUUCAGUGCUGGCUCCUUAUCUUGACUCUUUAGAACUGAAUGCAGUUCUUCAUUAAAAAAAAAACAAAACCUGUAUGUGUCCAUAGUCCCUAUAUUUCUGGUUCUCUUCCUGCUGGUAGUAAAUUAUUAUUUUCUUCUGAUUUAACUUCAGCUUGAAAAUCAUUUGUAAAGGCAAUAAAUAUUUGAGACAUUGAUCAUUUGAACCAUCAGCUGCUUUUCAUUGAGUCCCCAAAAUAUGCUAAUGUUUUUAGCAGAAAUCAGAGCACUUAAAAUAGAAGGCUUUGUUCUUGGUAUUUUUAUUUUAAAUAGCAGAGUUAAAUCUGUUUAUAUUACAUUUUUGUUUCACUAAUGUAGUUAGACUGACGUCUACAAUCUUUGGCAGGGGCAGGAUGGAAUAUAUCUAGGAUUUUCUAGCAGAGACUAAAUUGUUCAGUAUAUUUACCUUUUUUAAACAAGCAAAGACCUUACCAUUGUUUUUUUUUUACCACCUCUAGGCACAUUCCACCCUCUCAUCCCACAUUUCCCCAUUACUAUUAUGUAUUAUUUUUCCUGGUUCCACUUAAAAACACAAAAAUCCAUUAUUUUAAAUAUUUUCAUGUUCAUUACCUAAUACAUAUAAUUGUCAGGCUUUUUUUUUUCUUGCAUCUCACUUCCUGUAGUAUUCCUGUCACUGAUAGUUUGUGAAUGGGAAACUCUCUUAGUCUUUGUACAUCUGGAAAUGUCUUCAUUUUGUUCACAGUCUUUAGUGAUGGCUAAGCUAAGUAUAGAAUUCUAUACCCCUUUUCGCUUUGAAGAUCUAUCACUCAUUGCCUGCUGACAUCUAUUUUUGUUGAUAAGACAGCUGUUGUAAGACUAUUUGCUAUUUCUUUGAAGAUAAACUGUCUCCUUUCUUUUUCCUGCUGGCCUGUAAGAUUUUAUCUUCAUGCUUGAUAUACUAUAGAUUUACAGUGAUGUCUUCAGUGUGGAGUUUUAAAAACUUAUUCUACGUAGUACUCAGAAUACAUGUAAGAACUCCUGUCUUUAAGUAGUUCUAUAAAAUGAUCAGCUAUUAUAUAUUAAAUUUCCAUUAUCCCCACCCCCAUUUCCUCAUUCCGACCUUCUAUUAGACAUAUAUUGGUGAUGUAGUUUGAAUAUUUGUCCCCAUCCAAAUCUUAUGUUGAAUUUUAAUCCAAGAUUUUGGAGGUGGGUGGGGCCUGGUGGGAGGCUGUUUGGGUCACAGGGGUGUAUCUCUCAUGAAUGGCAUGGGCUAGCUCCUUGGUGAUAAGUGAGCACUCGCUCUGAGUUCACACAAGAUCUGCUAGUUUAAAAGUGUGUGGCACCCCCACCCCUCUCUCUUGCUUGCUCUGCUUUCUCCAUGUGAUGAGCCUGCUUCCCCUUCACCUUCUGCUAUGAUUGUAAGCUUCCUGAAGACUCCCUAGAAGCCAAGCAGAUGCCAGCACCAUGCUUCCUAUAAAGCCUGCAGAACCAUGAGCCAGUUAAACCUCUCUUAUUUAUAAAUUACCCAGUCUUAGAUAUUUCUCUAUAGCAAUGCAAGAAUGGUCUAAUACUAUUAGAGUCAUUCUUGCAUUCUCCUUGCCUAUUCUCCUUGUCUCUUAACUGUUUUUUCAUAUAUAUACAUAUAUACAUAUAUAUAUAUGUGAUUUGUAAAUACACACUCAUACUUACUUUUAUCUCAGAGCUGUAUCAGAAUAAAUUCCUCAGUACUAGAUCUUCCAGUUCACUCAUUCUGUUGUUUAUCUCCACUAUUGAGUUCUAUUUCAGUGGCUAUAUAUUUUCAUUUCCAAGGUAUCACAUUUUAAAAAUCUCUAUGAAGAUAUUAACAUAGCCUAUAAAUAUUCUUAGUUGGUUCUGUUAUUUUAUUUUUUUCUGAAAGUGCUUAUUCUUCUACUUGUUAAUUUUGUGGCUAAAUUAGAUGUCUUCAUGUGUUUUGGAAUUUUGAUUUGCAAGCUCACCUUGUUUAACAACUGUUUUCUCCUCCUUACUCCUUCCCACAACUUGCCCCACCCCCAUGGUAGUUUUGCAGCUGCUUCUGCAUCUAUAUCUGUGUUUUUCUAUUUCUCUAGAUGAGAAACCCCAUGUAAGUCGUAACUUGCAGCAUUUGUCAGCAACAAUUUUCUUUGGUUUCCUUUCAUAAACAUCAUGCAGUCUAAGUCCAGCCCCUCUGUUAAAAAAUUAAAAUAACAGAACAAAGUAAAAAGAUUUACAAGCUGUGUUUAAUGUCCUCAUUGUAUUAGUCCAUUCUCACACUGCUAUAAAGAACCGCCUUAGGCUGGAUAAUUUAUAAAGAAAAGAGGUUUAAUUGACUUACAGUUCCACGUGGCUGGGGAGGUCUCAGGAAAUUUAUAAUCAUGGUGGAAGGGGAAGCAAGGCAUGUCUUACAUGGCGGUGGGUGAGAGAGAGUGUGUGAAGGAGAAGCUGUGAAACACUUAUAAAACCAUCAGAUCUUGUGAGAACUCACCCACUGUCAAGAGAACAGCAUGGGGGAAACAGCACCCAGGAUUCAAUCACCUCCUACCAGGACACUCCCUCAACACUUGGGGAUUAUGGGGAUUACAAUUUGAGCUGAGAUUUGGGUGAAGACACAGAGCCAGACCAUAUCACUCAUAAUGAUUUUUUUUAAUUUGAUACCUUGGAAAUGAAAAGACCUUAACUUUAGCCCCACUAGGCACUCACGUGGCUUUAGCUCUGCCUCCACACUGUGUGCUUCUGGUCCAUGGAAGUGCUUAGCUUGUUUUCUGAGUAUAGCUAUUAGUUGGAAUUCUCUCAUUUUAUAUUUUAUCUGUCAUUGCCUGAUAUUUGAAGAAGGCAAAGACUUUUAGUGUAAUCUUUGGCUCUCUAUGAUUUAACCUUUGUUUUCAUUUCGUAUCUGUAGAAGGAAAAUAACAACUGCCCUUCCCAUCUGUGAAAGCACUUUGUGAGUAAAAAAGGCAAGUUGUGGCCAUUUGUAUAGUUAAUGUAAUUGGUAUCACAUUUUACCACUACACUCUACCUAUGGAGUCAAGGAUGUUCAGGAUGGGUGGGUGGCAUGCUAGGGGAAUGAAAUACCUUAUAUCAUAAUAGACUUCAACAUCCCUAAAGUUGUCUGCUAAAUGUUGUCAGUGGUUUAGUCCACAAAUUGCAGAGUGCUUUCUACAGGUAAAUGGAUUGUGACUGUGUAUUUACUUUUAGAGUUGCAUGCAAUGAAAAUGAAAUUGUUUUUCAUGACAGUAAAGCUGGCUCACUAUUCACUGGA